ACUCACUGUCACGAAAACAGCAUGGGGGAACUGCUCCCGUAAUCUAAUCACCUCCCAUGAGGUCCUUCCCCCAACACGUGGGGAUUACAAUUCAUAUUACAAUUCAAGGUGAGAUUUGGGUGGGGACACAGAGCCAGGCCAUAUCACAUUAUUAUUAAUUAGUGCCUUCUCUCUCAUUUUUUUGAUUCGCCUAGGUAGAGAUUUAUCAAUUUCAUUGAUCUUUUCGAAGAACCAAUUUUUGAUUUCAUUGAUUUUCCUCGAUUAAUUUUCUAUUUUUAAUUUCAUUGAUGUAUGCUCCAAUUUUGUAUUUUUUUCUUCUGCUUGUUUUAGACAUAUAUUGCUUUUCUGUUUCUAGUACUCUAGAUGGAAACAGAUUAUUGAUUUUAGAACUUUCUUUCUAAGAUAUACAUUCAAUAAUAUAAAUUUCCCUCUAAGCACUGCUUUUGCUACGUCUCACCGAUUUUGAUAGGCUAUAUUUUCAUUUUUAUUUAGUUAAAAAUAUUUUUAGUUUCUCUUGUGAUUUCUUCUUUGAUCCAUAUGUUAUUCGGAAGUGUGUUUUUAAAUCUCCAAAUACUUGGAAAUUUUCUGGCUUUCUUCCUGCUAGUGACUUCUAAUUUGAAUCCAUUGUGGCCUAAGAGCAUAUGUUGUGUGAUUUCUAAUGUUUUCAAUCUCUUAAGGUUGUUUUAUGUCCCAGAAUGUGGUCUGUCUUGGUGAUUAUUCCACAUGAACCUGAGGAGAAUGUAUAUUCUGCUGUUGUGAGAUGUAACAGUCUAUAAAUGGAUACCUCUGUUAAUAUGACCUCGGGUGACUCUUUUUUUUUUUUUAAGUUGCUGCUUCACCAUUGGCUUUUGGAGAUUUUGCAGAUGAUAAAAUCCUCAGGACUUUUCUGCUGCUCAGUCAGAUUUUCUUAUCCUACACUUGCGGAACUGUUGUUUGAAAUUGACAAGCAGGAUGGCCAACUCUGCCCGGCUCAUUUUAUUUCAUCUUAUUGGGUUCAGCCUGCAGUUUUAGGAGAUGAGAUUGAAGGAACUGGUAUACUGGAAUCCACGGUGGGCUCGGAAGCAAACAAACGUGCCUUGGCAUCUCCCAAUGGGGUGGCUUUGCUCUGGGCUCCUGUUCCCUGUGAGCUGCCUGGUCCUGCUGCAGGUGGCAAGCUCUGGGAACAUGAAGGUCUUGCAGGAGCCCACCUGCGUCUCCGACUACAUGAGCAUCUCUACUUGCGAGUGGAAGAUGAAUGGUCCCACCAAUUGCAGCACCGAGCUCCGCCUGUUGUACCAGCUGGUUUUUCUGCUCUCCGAAGCCCACACGUGUAUCCCUGAGAACAACGGAGGCGCGGGGUGCGUGUGCCACCUGCUCAUGGAUGACGUGGUCAGUGCGGAUAACUAUACACUGGACCUGUGGGCUGGGCAGCAGCUGCUGUGGAAGGGCUCCUUCAAGCCCAGCGAGCAUGUGAAACCCAGGGCCCCAGGAAACCUGACAGUUCACACCAAUGUCUCCGACACUCUGCUGCUGACCUGGAGCAACCCGUAUCCCCCUGACAAUUACCUGUAUAAUCAUCUCACCUAUGCAGUCAACAUUUGGAGUGAAAACGACCCGGCAGAUUUCAGAAUCUAUAACGUGACCUACCUAGAACCCUCCCUCCGCAUCGCAGCCAGCACCCUGAAGUCUGGGAUUUCCUACAGGGCACGGGUGAGGGCCUGGGCUCAGUGCUAUAACACCACCUGGAGUGAGUGGAGCCCCAGCACCAAGUGGCACAACUCCUACAGGGAGCCCUUCGAGCAGCACCUCCUGCUGGGCGUCAGCGUUUCCUGCAUUGUCAUCCUGGCCGUCUGCCUGUUGUGCUAUGUCAGCAUCACCAAGAUUAAGAAAGAAUGGUGGGAUCAGAUUCCCAACCCAGCCCGCAGCCGCCUCGUGGCUAUAAUAAUCCAGGAUGCUCAGGGGUCACAGUGGGAGAAGCGGUCCCGAGGCCAGGAACCAGCCAAGUGCCCACACUGGAAGAAUUGUCUUACCAAGCUCUUGCCCUGUUUUCUGGAGCACAACAUGAAAAGGGAUGAAGAUCCUCACAAGGCUGCCAAAGAGAUGCCUUUCCAGGGCUCUGGAAAAUCAGCAUGGUGCCCAGUGGAGAUCAGCAAGACAGUCCUCUGGCCAGAGAGCAUCAGCGUGGUGCGAUGUGUGGAGUUGUUUGAGGCCCCGGUGGAGUGUGAGGAGGAGGAGGAGGUAGAGGAAGAAAAAGGGAGCUUCUGUGCAUCGCCUGAGAGCAGCAGGGAUGACUUCCAGGAGGGAAGGGAGGGCAUUGUGGCCCGGCUAACAGAGAGCCUGUUCCUGGACCUGCUCGGAGAGGAGAAUGGGGGCUUUUGCCAGCAGGACAUGGGGGAGUCAUGCCUUCUUCCACCUUCGGGAAGUACGAGUGCUCACAUGCCCUGGGAUGAGUUCCCAAGUGCAGGGCCCAAGGAGGCACCUCCCUGGGGCAAGGAGCAGCCUCUCCACCUGGAGCCAAGUCCUCCUGCCAGCCCGACCCAGAGUCCAGACAACCUGACUUGCACAGAGACGCCCCUCGUCAUCGCAGGCAACCCUGCUUACCGCAGCUUCAGCAACUCCCUGAGCCAGUCACCGUGUCCCAGAGAGCUGGGUCCAGACCCACUGCUGGCCAGACACCUGGAGGAAGUAGAACCCGAGAUGCCCUGUGUCCCCCAGCUCUCUGAGCCAACCACUGUGCCCCAACCUGAGCCAGAAACCUGGGAGCAGAUCCUCCGCCGAAAUGUCCUCCAGCAUGGGGCAGCUGCAGCCCCCGUCUCGGCCCCCACCAGUGGCUAUCAGGAGUUUGUACAUGCGGUGGAGCAGGGUGGCACCCAGGCCAGUGCGGUGGUGGGCUUGGGUCCCCCAGGAGAGGCUGGUUACAAGGCCUUCUCAAGCCUGCUUGCCAGCAGUGCUGUGUCCCCAGAGAAAUGUGGGUUUGGGGCUAGCAGUGGGGAAGAGGGGUAUAAGCCUUUCCAAGACCUCAUUCCUGGCUGCCCUGGGGACCCUGCCCCAGUCCCUGUCCCCUUGUUCACCUUUGGACUGGACAGGGAGCCACCUCGCAGUCCGCAGAGCUCACAUCUCCCAAGCAGCUCCCCAGAGCACCUGGGUCUGGAGCCGGGGGAAAAGGUAGAGGACAUGCCAAAGCCCCCACUUCCCCAGGAGCAGGCCACAGACCCCCUUGUGGACAGCCUGGGCAGUGGCAUUGUCUACUCAGCCCUUACCUGCCACCUGUGCGGCCACCUGAAACAGUGUCAUGGCCAGGAGGAUGGUGGCCAGACCCCUGUCAUGGCCAGUCCUUGCUGUGGCUGCUGCUGUGGAGACAGGUCCUCGCCCCCUACAACCCCCCUGAGGGCCCCAGACCCCUCUCCAGGUGGGGUUCCACUGGAGGCCAGUCUGUGUCCGGCCUCCCUGGCACCCUCGGGCAUCUCAGAGAAGAGUAAAUCCUCAUCAUCCUUCCAUCCUGCCCCUGGCAAUGCUCAGAGCUCAAGCCAGACCCCCAAAAUCGUGAACUUUGUCUCCGUGGGACCCACAUACAUGAGGGUCUCUUAGGUGCAUGUCCUCUUGUUGCUGAGUCUGCAGAUGAGGACUAGGGCUUAUCCAUGCCUGGGAAAUGCCACCUCCUGGAAGGCAGCCAGGCUGGCAGAUUUCCAAAAGACUUGAAGAACCAUGGUAUGAAGGUGAUUGGCCCCACUGACGUUGGCCUAACACUGGGCUGCAGAGACUGGACCCCGCCCAGCAUUGGGCUGGGCUCGCCACAUCCCAUGAGAGUAGAGGGCACUGGGUCGCCGUGCCCCACGGCAGGCCCCUGCAGGAAAACUGAGGCCCUUGGGCACCUCGACUUGUGAACGAGUUGUUGGCUGCUCCCUCCACAGCUUCUGCAGCAGACUGUCCCUGUUGUAACUGCCCAAGGCAUGUUUUGCCCACCAGAUCAUGGCCCACGUGGAGGCCCACCUGCCUCUGUCUCACUGAACUAGAAGCCGAGCCUAGAAACUAACACAGCCAUCAAGGGAAUGACUUGGGCGGCCUUGGGAAAUCGAUGAGAAAUUGAACUUCAGGGAGGGUGGUCAUUGCCUAGAGGUGCUCAUUCAUUUAACAGAGCUUCCUUAGGUUGAUGCUGGAGGCAGAAUCCCGGCUGUCAAGGGGUGUUCAGUUAAGGGGAGCAACAGAGGACAUGAAAAAUUGCUAUGACUAAAGCAGGGACAAUUUGCUGCCAAACACCCAUGCCCAGCUGUAUGGCUGGGGGCUCCUCGUAUGCAUGGAACCCCCAGAAUAAAUAUGCUCAGCCACCCUGUGGGCCGGGCAAUCCAGACAGCAGGCAUAAGGCACCAGUUACCCUGCAUGUUGGCCCAGACCUCAGGUGCUAGGGAAGGCGGGAACCUUGGGUUGAGUAAUGCUCGUCUGUGUGUUUUAGUUUCAUCACCUGUUAUCUGUGUUUGCUGAGGAGAGUGGAACAGAAGGGGUGGAGUUUUGUAUAAAUAAAGUUUCUUUGUCUCUUUA